CCGGCUGGGCUCGGGCUCAGCUCGACUGGGCUCGGCGGGCGGCGGCGGCGGCGCCGGCGGCUGGCGGAGGAGGGAGGGCGAGGGCGGGCGCGGGCCGGCGGGCGGGCGGAAGAGGGAGGAGAGGCGCGGGGAGCCAGGCCUCGGGGCCUCGGAGCAACCACCCGAGCAGACGGAGUACACGGAGCAGCGGCCCCGGCCCCGCCAACGCUGCCGCCGGCUACUCCCUCUUGAUGCCCUCCCCUUUGCCCCUCACUCAGGAUGCUCCAGACCUUGUAUGAUUACUUCUGGUGGGAACGUCUGUGGCUGCCUGUGAACUUGACCUGGGCCGAUCUAGAAGACCGAGAUGGACGUGUCUACGCCAAAGCCUCAGAUCUCUAUAUCACGCUGCCCCUGGCCUUGCUCUUCCUCAUCGUUCGAUACUUCUUUGAGCUGUACGUGGCUACACCACUGGCUGCCCUCUUGAACAUAAAGGAGAAAACUCGGCUGCGGGCACCUCCCAACGCCACCUUGGAACAUUUCUACCUGACCAGUGGCAAGCAGCCCAAGCAGGUGGAAGUAGAGCUUUUGUCCCGGCAGAGCGGGCUCUCUGGCCGCCAGGUAGAGCGUUGGUUCCGUCGCCGCCGCAACCAGGACCGGCCCAGUCUCCUCAAGAAGUUCCGAGAAGCCAGCUGGAGAUUCACAUUUUACCUGAUUGCCUUCAUUGCCGGCAUGGCCGUCAUUGUGGAUAAACCCUGGUUCUAUGACAUGAAGAAAGUUUGGGAGGGAUAUCCCAUACAGAGCACUAUCCCUUCCCAGUAUUGGUACUACAUGAUUGAACUUUCCUUCUACUGGUCCCUGCUCUUCAGCAUUGCCUCUGAUGUCAAGCGAAAGGAUUUCAAGGAACAGAUCAUCCACCAUGUGGCCACCAUCAUUCUCAUCAGCUUUUCCUGGUUUGCCAAUUACAUCCGAGCUGGGACUCUAAUCAUGGCUCUGCAUGACUCUUCCGAUUACCUGCUGGAGUCAGCCAAGAUGUUUAACUACGCGGGAUGGAAGAACACCUGCAACAACAUCUUCAUCGUCUUCGCCAUUGUUUUUAUCAUCACCCGACUGGUCAUCCUGCCCUUCUGGAUCCUGCAUUGCACCCUGGUGUACCCACUGGAGCUCUAUCCUGCCUUCUUUGGCUAUUACUUCUUCAAUUCCAUGAUGGGAGUUCUACAGCUGCUGCAUAUCUUCUGGGCCUACCUCAUUUUGCGCAUGGCCCACAAGUUCAUAACUGGAAAGCUGGUAGAAGAUGAACGCAGUGACCGGGAAGAAACAGAGAGCUCAGAGGGGGAGGAGGCUGCAGCUGGGGGAGGAGCAAAGAGCCGGCCCCUAGCCAAUGGCCACCCCAUCCUCAAUAACAACCAUCGUAAGAAUGACUGAACCAUUACUCCAGCUGCCUCCCAGAUUAAUGCAUAAAGCCAAGGAACUACCCCGCUCCCUGCGCUAUAGGGUCACUUUAAGCUCUGGGGAAAAAGGAGAAAGUGAGAGGAGAGUUCUCUGCAUCCUCCCUCCUUGCUUGUCACCCAGUUGCCUUUAAACCAAAUUCUAACCAGCCUAUCCCCAGGUAGGGGGACGUUGGUUAUAUUCUGUUAGAGGGGGACGGUCGUAUUUUCCUCCCUACCCGCCAAGUCAUCCUUUCUACUGCUUUUGAGGCCCUCCCUCAGCUCUCUGUGGGUAGGGGUUACAAUUCACAUUCCUUAUUCUGAGAAUUUGGCCCCAGCUGUUUGCCUUUGACUCCCUGACCUCCAGAGCCAGGGUUGUGCCUUAUUGUCCCAUCUGUGGGCCUCAUUCUGCCAAAGCUGGACCAAGGCUAACCUUUCUAAGCUCCCUAACUUGGGCCAGAAACCAAAGCUGAGCUUUUAACUUUCUCCCUCUAUGACACAAAUGAAUUGAGGGUAGGAGGAGGGUGCACAUAACCCUUACCCUACCUCUGCCAAAAAGUGGGGGCUGUACUGGGGACUGCUCGGAUGAUCUUUCUUAGUGCUACUUCUUUCAGCUGUCCCUGUAGCGACAGGUCUAAGAUCUGACUGCCUCCUCCUUUCUCUGGCCUCUUCCCCCUUCCCUCUUCUCUUCAGCUAGGCUAGCUGGUUUGGAGUAGAAUGGCAACUAAUUCUAAUUUUUAUUUAUUAAAUAUUUGGGGUUUUGGUUUUAAAGCCAGAAUUACGGCUAGCACCUAGCAUUUCAGCAGAGGGACCAUUUUAGACCAAAAUGUACUGUUAAUGGGUUUUUUUUAAAAAUUAAAAGAUUAAAUAAAAAAUAUUAAAUAAAACAUGGCAAUAAGUGUCAGACUAUUAGGAAUUGAGAAGGGGGAUCAACUAAAUAAACGAAGAGAGUCUUUCUUA